AGCGUGCCCCGCGGCGGGCCCUACCGGCCGCGACUCCGGGCUUGGCCCCGGCCCUAGCUCGUCGGCUGUGUAUUGGGGCGCGUGGAGGCUGCAGUCACGGUGGCGCCCGCGGGGACGGAGGAGGGAAUGAGUGAAGAGGAGCAAGGCUCCGGCACUACCACGGGCUGCGGGCUGCCUAGUAUAGAGCAAAUGCUGGCCGCCAACCCAGGCAAGACCCCGAUCAGCCUUCUGCAGGAGUAUGGGACCAGAAUAGGGAAGACGCCUGUGUACGACCUUCUCAAAGCCGAGGGCCAAGCCCACCAGCCUAAUUUCACCUUCCGGGUCACCGUUGGCGACACCAGCUGCACUGGUCAGGGCCCCAGCAAGAAGGCAGCCAAGCACAAGGCAGCUGAGGUGGCCCUCAAACACCUCAAAGGGGGGAGCAUGCUGGAGCCGGCCCUGGAGGACAGCAGUUCUUUUUCUCCCCUAGACUCUUCACUGCCUGAGGACAUUCCGGUUUUUACUGCUGCAGCAGCUGCUACCCCAGUUCCAUCUGUAGUCCUAACCAGGAGCCCCCCCAUGGAACUGCAGCCCCCUGUCUCCCCUCAGCAGUCUGAGUGCAACCCCGUUGGUGCUCUGCAGGAGCUGGUGGUGCAGAAAGGCUGGCGGUUGCCGGAGUACACAGUGACCCAGGAGUCUGGGCCAGCCCACCGCAAAGAAUUCACCAUGACCUGUCGAGUGGAGCGUUUCAUUGAGAUUGGGAGUGGCACUUCCAAAAAAUUGGCAAAGCGGAAUGCGGCGGCCAAAAUGCUGCUUCGAGUGCACACGGUGCCUCUGGAUGCCCGGGAUGGCAAUGAGGUGGAGCCUGAUGAUGACCACUUCUCCAUUGGUGUGGGCUCCCGCCUGGAUGGUCUUCGAAACCGGGGCCCAGGUUGCACCUGGGAUUCUCUACGAAAUUCAGUAGGAGAGAAGAUCCUGUCCCUCCGCAGUUGCUCCCUGGGCUCCCUGGGUGCCCUGGGCCCUGCCUGCUGCCGUGUCCUCAGUGAGCUCUCUGAGGAGCAGGCCUUUCACGUCAGCUACCUGGAUAUUGAGGAGCUGAGCCUGAGUGGACUCUGCCAGUGCCUGGUGGAACUGUCCACCCAGCCGGCCACUGUGUGUCAUGGCUCUGCAACCACCAGGGAGGCAGCCCGUGGUGAGGCUGCCCGCCGUGCCCUGCAGUACCUCAAGAUCAUGGCAGGCAGCAAGUGAAGCCCCAGCUGGACUCAUGGAUGUGCACCCUUUGCUCCCUGCUCUUUCUGCCUCUGGGCUCAUGUAUCUGCGCAGCUCUGGUACCCUCUGUGGGUGCCAUCUCUACCUCUGACACAGACUGCCUGCCUUGAAGCUGAGAAGGCACAGGGCAAGGAGCCAAGGACCACAGAGCCUCAGCCAGCCCAGGAUCCGUCCUCAUUUUAUUGGUGAUGAUGAAUGGGAAUGAAAUCAGGGGGCUGUCUACUAGAGCCUGGAAUAAAUAUGCUGCUUUGUGGAUUUUUAA